CCAGAGCUCAACGUUCCCUAAGUGAGUGGCCUUUGACAGCAGUGCCAGGCAGCCCAGUGGGUGCAGGGCACACCACAGAUGGAGGAAGGGCCAGGCAUGCUUCCCAGACAGCCUCUGCCAGUCCAGGCAGGGGCUCCAGGGUGGCUGCGGGAAGGCAGCUUAGGCGGUGCCCGGCCCAAGGCUCCGUCCUUCUUCCCCGUGGUGGCCCCAGCCUCCCUGCCAAGCUUCCCGGCCCCCGCCCCAUCCCGGGCCUGCUGCUGCGGAGACCGUGGGCCGGCGCUGGACGGCGCGGCCUCCAGAAGUGAUAGCUAAUUGGGGAGAGAAAGGGCCCAAUUGUCUGGCGGGGCCGGAAGAGCCGCGUGGGCUGCUGAAAGCGUCGGGAGGAGGUGGCCGCUUCGCCCAGCAGCUGCCGCCGGGGAUGUUUGCAGAUUACGUCAGCGCUGGCGAGCAGGGGGCGCGGGGACAGCGAGGGGGGCGGGCUCCCGGCGGCCUCCCGCCCCCCAGGCCCCUGGACAAUGCUGUCAUUGUCAGCACGGAGAGUGGUUAAUUCUGGAUGAAUGGUACACGGGCCUCUUGACCAAGGAGGCUGCUCGUCGUCCCCAGUCUGUCCUCUCACAUGCCAGGGAGGCCCCGGGCUGGAGUCUGGCGGGCAGAUCUGGCCUGCUUGGUGGCACCAGAGAGAACAGGGCGGUCCCUUGGGGGCGCCGGCUGCAGAGGCCCCAGGCUGGACGGAGCUUCCUGUCCUGGGUCUGCACAGCAGCCACUUGGCAGUGCCGGGCUAGGGUGGCAGGGCCCCACUGCAUCUCGGUUCCAGGGCAGAGGCUGCUGCUGCCCUUUGGGGCUGACUUCAGGCAUGACCUCCUGGCCAGGUGGCAGCUUUGGCCCUGACCCGCUCCUGGCCCUGCUGGUGGUGAUCCUGCUAGCACGCCUCAUCCUGUGGUCCUGCCUCGGGACCUACAUCGACUACAGACUGGCCCAGCGGCGGCCCCAGAAACCCAAGCAGGACUAAGCCUCUGCAGGCUGCGGCCUCCACGCGCCCUGUCCCGAGACUCAGCCGGCCCUUCCAGUGGUGGUGGGAGGGAGGGGAGCAGGGCAGGCGCAUGAUCCCCAUGUCCCACCCCUGGGGCAGGAGCUCAGAGAGGCCUGAGAUGGAUCGUGCCUUCCCAGACUGACCAGGGCUGUCCCGUAGAGGCAGCUGGCCAUGUGGGGAGAUGGAGGGGCCGGCCUUGCAGGUCCAUCACCAGGUUCUGGGGUCCCCGGUUGCAGGGAGUGGUCCUGGGGGUGGGUCUUGCUUUAAGACCUUCUCUGCCUCCAAUUCCUUAUAAAUAUGCCUGCAGGAAGAGCUGGGUAAGCCAGAGGACUCAGGUGGAGGUGCCACAGAGACAAAUGUGACCUCAUCACAAGCUGGCCCUGUUACCAAAGGCCACGUCCUGUCUCAGCUCACCACCCUCAUAACUAGUCUCCUCCUGCCUCCCAAGGGACGAGAUAAGUGCCGAUGGCUGUCCUGAUUUCUCCAGAGCAGACCCCUGGGAAGGGUCUCAGGACGCACUUGUGAGGCUGAGUUGACAAGCCAGACGCACUUGGCUCUGGUUGACCCUCUGCACACUCUCUAACGGUCUGAACAGUUAGGGCACAAUGAUCCCUGCCUCCCUCCCUCAGCAGGAUAUCAUGUAGGGGACAAUUUAGGGGACAAGCCAAGGCACCCAUCAAUGCCCUCUGUUCAUCUGUUCCUGCAAGUGUGUGGCUGGGAAGUGCCCAGGAAGGCUGACAGGGCAGGGAAGUUGAUUUGAGGCCAAGCAUCCAGUGCUCCUGCUCCACCUCCGUAGCACGUUAGCCGUGAUGCCAGUGACUUAACCCACAGCUUGGGGAAGCUCAAAGGCUCCACAUUCGAGCCUCUUGGGGGAAAUUCGGCAAACACCCAUGUCCAAGUUCCACACUGUAUUUCCUGGGAUCGUUCCAGCAGAUCGUGGAUUGCAGCGAGGGCUGCUGACUGCAUGCGGAACUGUGAGAUGGAAGGGACUGUGGGCGGCAGCUCCAGGGAGGAGCAUCGAACCAGAUAUCGUCUCUGGGAGGCUGGGCCUGGUGAUGUGGCAACGUCUUGCUCCCUGAGAGGUGAUGGGUAUGCUAGGGAUGCUCGCUCAGGGAACGUGGGCCAAGUCCUCUGAACACGAAGCUCGCAGAGGGGGUGAUUCCUGUGAAUUCUGAAAGGACUUGGGGGCGUCCAGCAAGAGCAGGAGCUUAGAUGGUGGUUCCAGGGCUGGUGUUGCUGACUGGGACGAGUGGACCCCCAGGGUGGGCAUGGAGUGGGGCACUGGCUGGGAGCCUCUGCCUUGCUGUGUCCUGGCUGAAUGAACCCAGGACUUGCUGUGCUCAGAUCCUCCAUUCAAGAGAGCUACAGACACGGGGGUGCUGGUGAGCAGGAGCCGAGACCAUCUGGGGUGGGACCGACCAAGAGUUUGAGGUGUCCAGGGGGUGACGUGAAGAUGACCUAUUGCAGAGGGUCCCUUCUCAUUCACGCUCUGAAGUCUGCACAGGGGCAGGGGCUACCGUGCUCCAUUUCAGUUUGGCCUCUGUUGUAUCAGCCAGAGGCCAGCAGAACUCUAUGGUCACUCCCCCGUGUCACGGACAAUUUGCCACCUCCACCGGCAGCCCAGGGCUCUGCCUGAAUAUUCUCGCCUGAUCGUAGGAUUGUGGGGAGGGAUAUUCUCAUUGAUCUCUAAGGAAAAUAUUGUUCGCUUUUUAAAAACAUGAUCUGGUACCAUUUCAUUGAUCUCUUUAAGGAAGAAAAAUCACAUGGUUGUCAUGAGCAUGUACCGACAGAGCUAGGAGGGCCAGCUGUUCCGGGUUGCCCAGGGCUGUCUUGUUUUUAAAAUGGAAAGUUCGAUGUCCUGGAAAACCCCUCAGUCCUGGGCAAACCAGGUCACGCUGGAUAGAAGGAGUUAGACAUUCAUAUGAUGUGCCGAUGUCUUGCCAGUUGUAGAGUUUUGUGUAAACCUGUGUGUGGCCUGCGUGUCCACAUGGGUGUGUAGGAUGGCACCUACACACAUACCUGAGGUCACCUCUUGGUCCAGUGAGCCAGAAUCCUGGGACUUCAUCAUCUUUUUUUUUUUUUUUUUUGAGAUGGAAUCUCACUCUGUCACCCAGGCUGGAGGGCAGUGGCGCAAUCUUGGCUCACUGCAACCUCCGCCUCUGGGGCUCAAGCAAUUCUCCUGCCUCAGCCUCCCGAGUAGCUGGGAUUAUAGGCGUGUGCCACCACGCCCUGCUGAUUUUUGUAUUUUUUAGUAGAGAUGGUGUUUCACUAUAUUGGCCAGGCUGGUCUUGAACUCCUGACCUCAAGUGAUCUGCCUGCCUUGGCCUCCCGAAAUGCUGGGGUUACAGGCAUGAGCUACCAUGCCCGGCCUCAGAAUCCUGGGACUUCUGCUGGAGCCAGGGGUCAGAACAGACUCCUCUACUGGGACUGCCUGGCAGGGAGGACAGACGCUCAAGGCGGCCCCAUGAGAACACAGCCACCUGGAAAAAUGGUGGAAGGGAAGAUUCUGCCAACCUCCUCCGACUCCCUAUCUCAGUUACACUGGUCCAUAAUUUCUUUUCUUUUUCUUAAGUCUGUUUCAUUGGUUUCUGUUCCUGGAAAAUGGACACAAUUCUGAUGAAUUCAUGUAUUCUGCAUCCACGUGUCAGCAUCUCCAGCCUUGUGACGCAGUGCCUGGCUCAGAACAGGCAAUCAGGCCAUGGCAUCUGAAUGAAUGAGAGGGUGUGCCCUGGCCGUAUCUCAGGCAGCAGAUGCAUUCAGCUGCAGGUAACAGACACGUAGACAAACAGUGGCUUAAAAAAGAGAGGCUUUAAAAGUAUUUUGUUUUUCUUUCUUCACGUAGCAAGAAGUCUGGCAUUUGGCAUUCCCAGGCUGUGGCGUGACAGCUUUGUGAAGUUAUCAGGGUCUCAGACCCUGACAUAUUUCUGCUCUGCUACCCUCAGCAUGUAGAUUUGAUCUUCACGGCUACAAGAAACCUGCUGCUACUGCAGGCAUCUUACACGAGUUCCAGGCAGGAAGAGAAAGGAAAGGGUGACAGAGACAGAAAGCAAUGUCCCCAGAUACCCUUAGUUUUCCAUCUCAUAAGCCAGAAUGAUGUCACGUGGCAUCCCUGGAUGCACAGGAGGCUGAGAGAUAGUGGCGUUUGUUAGCUGGUCUCCUAGCCAUCCUGAAUGCCAAGUUUGUUAUAAAGAAACAGAGGCAAAAUGGCGAUCAGGCAGGCAACUGGGUGGUCUCUGCCACGGGCCCCUUGGCCAUUCUUUGUAAUGAUGGUCUUUGUCUUGGACCCUAUUUUGGAUAUUUGGGCACCUUUGUGGUACCCUUAUGUGCUGGUUUUGCUGUUGUCUGCCCUUCAGGAAUAGCAGCUGAGUCAAGCUGUCCUUGGCUGCUCCAAUCUGGAGUCAGAGGUUGGAGAUUUCCAUGGCUCCCCAUGGCUCCUUGGGGCCUCCUAAGAAAAUGUUUUAAUAAGGAAGUCCAAGGCUGAGACAGACAUGCUCCUUCUUAGAGACACAUGGGAACAUGCCUCUGCUCACAGCUGGUAGCCACAGAUGUAAACCGUAGCCCAUGGAACGGAGACAGUGAAGAAUUGAUGGAUAAAUGAAUAAUGAUGAUGGACAGCAGAUGUAUAAAAGGCAUAAAAGGAUAGUGUUAGGGCUGGAAUGUCUUCCCCCCAAUUCAUAUGUUGAACCUUUAAUGCCUAAUACUUCAGAAAGAGACUGUGUUUGAAGAUAUGGUCUUUACAGAGGGAAUAAAGUUAAAAUAAGGUCAUUAGGGUGAGCCCUAAUCCAAAGGAUGGGUGUCCUAAUCAGAGGAGGAGAUUAGGACCCAGACACACACACACACACAGAGCCAGGUGAGGACACAGGGAGAAAAUGGCCACGUACAAGCCAAGAUGAGAGGACUCAGGAAGAACCAGCCGACUCCACCCUUCAAAACUGUGAGAACAUAGAUGUCUGCUGUUUGAGCCACCCUGUCUGCAAGCAGUCAGCAAGCAUUCAUUGAGUGCUUGCAGUAUUCAAGGCACCACAGAUACAAUGUUGAAUAAGGCAAAGCACCUGCCCUCAGGUAGCUUGCAGUCAGGGAGGUAAGGGUAGUGGGCAGAGAGACCUGGAAACAGAUAUUAGACCUGCACUAAGCAUGUGUGGUUAUUGAACAGUAAAAAUGCCACCACAAAUUGCGAUAUGAUGUAAGUAAAAUGCGUACUGGCUAUUGAAGACUUGGCACAGAAAAAUAAUGUAAAAUCUCAUUAGUAAUGGUUUUAUAUUGAUUACGCAUUGAAAUAAUACUAUUUUGGACAGAUUGGGUUAAAUAAAAUAUUAAAUUUGA